GCCGGGCCCGCUCACGGCCGCGUGGGAGCAGUGGGGUUCGACGGCGCGGCCGCGAGGCCGCCAUGGCCGCUCACGGGAAGCUGCGGCGGGAGCGGGGGCUGCAGGCUGAGUAUGAGACGCAAGUCAAAGAGAUGCGCUGGCAGCUGAGCGAGCAGCUGCGCUGCCUGGAGCUGCAGGGCGAGCUGCGGCGGGAGUUGCUGCAGGAGCUGGCAGAGUUCAUGCGGCGCCGCGCUGAGGUGGAGCUGGAAUACUCCCGGGGCCUGGAAAAGCUGGCCGAGCGCUUCUCCAGCCGUGGAGGCCGCCUGGGGAGCAGCCGGGAGCACCAAAGCUUCCGGAAGGAGCCGUCCCUCCUGUCGCCCUUGCACUGCUGGGCGGUGCUGCUGCAGCACACGCGGCAGCAGAGCCGGGAGAGCGCGGCCCUGAGUGAGGUGCUGGCCGGGCCCCUGGCCCAGCGCCUGAGUCACAUUGCAGAGGACGUGGGGCGCCUGGUCAAGAAGAGCAGGGAUCUGGAGCAGCAGCUGCAGGAUGAGCUCCUGGAGGUGGUCUCAGAGCUCCAGACGGCCAAGAAGACGUACCAGGCAUAUCACAUGGAGAGCGUGAAUGCCGAGGCCAAGCUCCGGGAGGCCGAGCGGCAGGAGGAGAAGCGGGCAGGCCGGAGUGUCCCCACCACCACCGCUGGUGCCACUGAGGCAGGGCCCCUCCGCAAGAGCUCCCUCAAGAAGGGAGGGAGGCUGGUGGAGAAGCUCUGGCCCCCGCAGAGGCCUGUGGCCGCUUCCAGCUGUGCACCUGUGUGCUGGCUCCAAGCUGGGUUUCUCGUGCACCCUCCAUGGUGGGGUGCCAUGUGCGCACCUUCCACUCAUCAGCGGCAGGCCAAGUUCAUGGAGCACAAACUCAAGUGCACAAAGGCGCGCAACGAGUACCUGCUUAGCCUGGCUAGUGUCAACGCUGCUGUCAGUAACUACUACCUGCAUGACGUCUUGGACCUCAUGGACUGCUGUGACACAGGGUUCCACCUGGCCCUGGGGCAGGUGCUCCGGAGCUACACGGCCGCUGAGAGCCGCACCCAAGCCUCCCAAGUGCAGGGCCUGGGCAGCCUGGAAGAAGCUGUGGAGGCCCUGGAUCCUCCAGGGGACAAAGCCAAGGUUCUCGAGGUGCAUGCUACCGUCUUCUGUCCCCCGCUGCGCUUUGACUACCACCCCCAUGAUGGGGAUGAGGUGGCUGAGAUCUGCGUUGAAAUGGAGCUGCGGGACGAGAUUCUGCCCAGAGCCCAGAACAUCCAGAGCCGCCUGGACCGACAGACCAUUGAGACAGAGGAGGUGAACAAGACUCUGAAGGCGACACUGCAGGCCCUGCUGGAGGUGGUGGCCUCGGAUGACGGGGAUGUGCUUGAUUCCUUCCAGACCAGCCCCUCCACCGAGUCCCUCAAGUCCACCAGCUCAGACCCAGGCAGCCGGCAGGCGGGCCGGAGGCGCGGCCAGCAGCAGGAGACCGAAACCUUCUACCUCACGAAGCUCCAGGAGUAUCUGAGUGGACGGAGCAUCCUCGCCAAGCUGCAGGCCAAGCACGAGAAGCUGCAGGAGGCCCUUCAGCGAGGUGACAAGGAGGAGCAGGAGGUGUCUUGGACCCAGUACACACAGAGAAAAUUCCAGAAGAGCCGCCAGCCCCGCCCCAGCUCCCAGUAUAACCAGAGACUCUUUGGGGGAGACAUGGAGAAGUUUAUCCAGAGCUCAGGCCAGCCUGUGCCCCUGGUGGUGGAGAGCUGCAUUCGCUUCAUCAACCUCAAUGGCCUGCAGCAUGAAGGCAUCUUCCGGGUAUCGGGUGCCCAGCUCCGGGUCUCAGAGAUCCGUGAUGCCUUCGAGAGAGGGGAGGACCCACUGGUGGAGGGCUGCACUGCCCAUGACCUGGACUCGGUGGCCGGGGUGCUGAAGCUCUACUUCCGGAGCCUGGAGCCCCCACUCUUCCCCCCAGACCUGUUCGGCGAGCUGCUGGCUUCUUCGGAGCUGGAGGCCACAGCGGAGAGGGUGGAGCACGUGAGCCGCCUGCUGUGGCGGCUGCCCGCGCCGGUGCUGGUGGUUCUGCGCUACCUCUUCACCUUCCUCAACCACCUGGCCCAGUACAGCGAUGAGAACAUGAUGGACCCCUACAACCUGGCCGUGUGCUUCGGGCCCACGCUGCUACCGGUGCCCGCUGGGCAGGACCCGGUGGCGCUGCAGGGCCGGGUGAACCAGCUGGUGCAGACGCUCAUAGUGCAGCCCGAUCGGGUCUUCCCGCCCCUGACCUCGCUGCCUGGCCCCGUCUACGAGAAGUGCAUGGCACCGCCUUCCGCCAGCUGCCUGGGGGACGCCCAGCUGGAGAGCCUGGGGGCGGACAAUGAGCCGGAGCUGGAAGCCGAGAUGCCCGCACAGGAGGAUGACCUGGAGGGGGUCGUGGAGGCUGUGGCCUGCUUUGCCUACACGGGCCGCACAGCCCAGGAGCUGAGCUUCCGGCGGGGGGACGUACUGCGGCUGCACGAGAGGGCCUCGAGCGACUGGUGGCGGGGGGAGCACAACGGCAUGCGGGGCCUCAUCCCCCACAAGUAUAUCACGCUGCCCGCCGGGACGGAGAAGCAGGUGGUGGGCGCAGGGCUGCAGACUGCAGGGGAGUCUGGGAGCAGUCCCGAGGGCCUCCUGGCAUCGGAGCUGGUCCACCGGCCAGAGCCAUGCACCUCACCUGAGGCCAUGGGACCCUCUGGACACAGACGACGCUGCUUGGUCCCAGCCUCCCCAGAGCAACACGUGGAGGUGGAUAAGGCUGUGGCACAGAACAUGGACUCUGUGUUUAAGGAGCUCUUGGGAAAGACCUCUGUCCGCCAGGGCCUUGGGCCAGCAUCUACCACCUCUCCCAGUCCUGGGCCCCGAAGCCCAAAGGCCCCGCCCAGCAGCCGCCUGGGCAGGAACAAAGGCUUCUCCCGGGGCCCUGGGGCCCCAGCCUCACCCUCAGCUUCCCACCCCCAGGGCCUAGACACGACCCCCAAGCCACACUGAGGUGCCGCUGCUGGAGAUGCGUGCCCCCGGCGGCUACCCGCUGGACCGGCCACUCUCCCCAGCCCCCUUGCUUCUCUCCAGCCCUGUCCAGCAAGUGCAGGGUGCCUGCACUUCACCCUGUGCAGAGAGGUGGGAUGGGGCCGUGCACACAGGGAUGCCCGCUCCACAUCCUGCCUGCCCCUCAGCCCUGGCCCAGGCCCCUUUUGGAGGCAGCUGAGGAAGGAUGCUGGGGAAAGCCCUCUUCUGCAGCUUUGUGGAAGGCUGAUCAGUGGCUGCUGGGUGGCGGGUACCCUUGCUCAGAUGCCUGGCAGGGCUGGGUGGCGAUUCAUAAAGACCUCGUGUUGAUUCCCC